AGCAGUAGCACCAGCGGCUGCGGCGGCGGAGCUCCUCCGAGGUCCGGGUCACCAGUCUCUGCUCUUCCCAGCCUCUCCGGCGCGCUCCAAGGGCUUCCCGUCGGGACCAUGCGCGGCCGUGAGCUCCCGCUGGUCCUGCUGGCGCUGGUCCUCUGCCUGGCGCCCCGGGGGCGAGCGGUCCCGCUGCCUGCGGGCGGAGGGACCGUGCUGACCAAGAUGUACCCGCGCGGCAACCACUGGGCGGUGGGGCACUUAAUGGGGAAAAAGAGCACAGGGGAGUCUUCUUCUGUUUCUGAGAGAGGGAGCCUGAAGCAGCAGCUGAGAGAGUACAUCAGGUGGGAAGAAGCUGCAAGGAAUUUGCUGGGUCUCAUAGAAGCAAAGGAGAACAGAAACCACCAGCCACCUCAACCCAAGGCCCUGGGCAAUCAGCAGCCUUCGUGGGAUUCAGAGGAUAGCAGCAACUUCAAAGAUGUAGGUUCAAAAGGCAAAGUUGGUAGACUCUCUGCUCCAGGUUCUCAACGUGAAGGAAGGAACCCCCAGCUGAACCAGCAAUGAUAAUGAUGGCCUCUCUCAAAAGAGAAAAACAAAACCCCUAAGAGACUGCGUUCUGCAAGCAUCAGUUCUACGGAUCAUCAACAAGAUUUCCUUGUGCAAAAUAUUUGACUAUUCUGUAUCUUUCAUCCUUGACUAAAUUCGUGAUUUUCAAGCAGCAUCUUCUGGUUUAAACUUGUUUGCUGUGAACAAUUGUCGAAAAGAGUCUUCCAAUUAAUGCUUUUUUAUAUCUAGGCUACCUGUUGGUUAGAUUCAAGGCCCCGAGCUGUUACCAUUCACAAUAAAAGCUUAAACACAUUGUCCAAA